GAGCGUGGCUGUGGGUGAUGGGUGGGUCAGGGACCCGGGCAGGAUGUGCGGUGUCCGGAGGCAUCCGGGCUCAGCAUUGUUUUCUCCCACCUCCUUCAACGCCAAACCUUCCUUCCUUAUCCGGAGGUUCCCAGACUCAGCUGUCAGCCACGAGACGCACAAGUGACUUUUUCUCCCCACUGACGGCAGAGGAAAAGUUCCGCUCUGCGUCUUUGCGUUCUGAUGGAUGCUUUCCCUCAUUUUCUCUGCAAGCUUCACUAAACCGUUGAUGGAGGGAGGAAGGGAGAACUCUGGAUAAAUGCAGACCCACCGGAUGGUUGUGCAUUGCUUUCCAAUGAAGGGUUAGCUUUUCCCAUACAAUGAAGAAAAUGCACAGCUUACUCUCAAGUGUAAAAAAAGAAUCCCUCUAGACUUAAAUGAUCCCGAAAUCCCAAGAUGUGUGAACUUUCCCGGUAGGGAGGCAGAGUUUUAAGUGGACCCUGCAUCACAGUAAAGAGCAAUGCAAGAGCCCAGAGUUUUUGCGCUGCAGAAAGCACAACCGGAAAGCAAUCAAUCCCCCAAGCAUUAUCACUGGUCCUUGUGGUUACCACCACAUCCAGGGAAAACGCUUCCUGACCCGCUAAUCACCUCACAGAAUUUCUCUCCAUCCAUUUGGCAAGGAAUUUGUAAACCUCUUUCCUCCCCUUUCUCUUUCCAUCUUCCUUCCACUUGGGGCUUGUUUCUUCUGUUCGAGAUUUCCUCUUUUGGGAGCAUGACUUUGGGGUAAGGUUAUUUAGGAAAGAACCCUCGCACAGGCUCUGGAAAAGGGCCUCAGUGUAAAUGCAUGUGAGUAAUCAAUCAAAUGUAUGUCAGAUUAAAAUUGAUUUUGGUGGAGCAGUCAGUAUAAAACGAUAUGUAUGUAUGUAUAUAUGUAAGUAUAUAUGUGUGUGUGUACAUACACACACACACAUCCCUCAAUGACAAUGAAAGAUGGACUUUUACUUACUAUUGAAUUUAUUGGGUUCACUAAUAUAUUCAAAAGCUCUGUUCAGGGUUAAGCUGCGUAACCAGUGCAUCACGCAUGUUGCAAGCUCCCAGCACCAGCUUAGGUAGACUAACCACAGAAUGUGGCUCCAGUAAAGUCUUUUUCCCAACACUGACACAUGGAAGUUUAAAAUCAGUGGAGAGGUUUCUAUAAUAUAUAAAGAAGAGUGGGUGGUAAUUACAAAUGGCUUGUAGUAGUUUCUGUUAUUUUGUGGCUUUUUGAUUAUGUAACAGGAGUGUUCUAUUCUGGGUGUGAAUUUGGACAAAGGGAAAUUACUAUUUUGUUUUUAACCCACAGGUCAGAAAGCACACUGUUUUCAAACUUAAAAAACAUCACAAUUAGGAAACACAUACAUUUUGGAUUCUACUGUAUUGAUACUACAUGGUGUCCUGUGUGUGUAAAACAGGCACUGCAAGAGACUUUAAAAUAUAUGACAAUAAAGAGCAAACGGCUCUAUAAUGUUGUAAAAAACAAAAGUAAUGGAGUAUAAGGAAUAUACAAAUUCUUGCAACUGAGUUUGCCACUUGUGAAUUGUACUAUGCUGGUUUAUAUUCUCAGAAGGGUCAUUGCUGAGUAAUGGUGCCUCUUUUGUUUUGAAGUUUCUUUUUGUGACAAAAAAGGAGGGAGACAACAGAAUAUUAACUUGAUUUUUCCCCUAUUUAAUAGUAAAUGCAAUUAACAUUUGGUAAAUGGCCUUUAAAAUUAAAGAUAUUAGAAAAUAAAGUGAAUUAUUAUGUUAGGUUUUUAUUGGAAAAGUAGCACAUACAUAUAAUUUAAAAAAUCAAAUGUUGCAAAGGAGUGUGAAGGAAAGACCCUCAGACACUCCACAUUCCCACUUAUGUAGUCCACCCUCAUAGAUGUUAACACUUUCUUAUGUAUGCUUCCAAAAUAUUCCAUGCAUGUGUAAGCAGAUAUAUCUAUAUGUGUCUAUGAUGAACUAUAGCAGCUCCUGAUUUCUACAAAAAAAUCUGGCUAGAGUUUUACAAGUCUCAUAGUUUUAAGCAUUUUUGAAGCCUAGAGGGGGUAAUCUGGUAGGUCUUUGGUGGGCAGCAGUCAUUGGGGUCUGUUCCCAGAGGCCUUAACGCCCUUCUAAGGAGAAAAAAAGGCAGGUGGUAAGCUCUGUUCCACUCCGUCUCUGAGAUCAAGAACCUUUCUGGUGACAUUCUUGAAUCUGCUGCCCUGUGGUUUGUUCCCUUUAGCAUAGUAAAAAUGAGUUUCCAAAAAAAGUUUAGAUCAUAUAAGAAAUACAUAGCACAUGUUCUAUAUUGAGAGAAAAUGCAUUUUUCACAGUUUUGCCAAGAGAUUUUUUUUUAAAUUUGGCAUUGAAAUGUACACAAAGAAGAAAAGCUUUAGUACAUUUUAAUCAAAAUAUUAAAUGCUGUUCCAAAUAGCUGUAGUGCAGUAAUAAUUGAUAUUCAUAAUGCUGAGCCACUGAAAGGUUGUGAAUCAUCAAAUAUUAAAUUCUUGUCAGCUCAAUUUAAGGUAUUGUUUCAGAAUAGUGCUAUCCUGACAGAAAACAGACUGUCUUGUAUAUUAAUAAAAAGAAUGUUUUUAGUAAAUUUGCCCUCCAUAAUUUGUGAAAACAUGUGUUUAGUUGAAAAAACAAUUUUCUUCUGAGCUGAGGAAAACAAUGACAACAUUUAUCUGUAUGCAUCUUCAGAAAUUCUUUCUACUGACAUUGUGUUUCUUCCCCACAUAUAACCAAUCCUAGGUUUAAAAACGUUCAAUGUGAGAAUUAAACUAAGUUUUUUUAAAAUCUGUCUACUUUUUCCUAUAUUUUUCUGUGUGAUUGUUUCAACAGCAUUGACAUUGAUAAAUGCUGCAUGUUUUUUGGUAAGCGCAUUGUUAUAUACCACAAUAAUGCAAUAGAAUCCAUUUUAAUUUCUUCUUGAUGACUUGUGGUUUGAAAUGACAAGUUGGAUACCUGCAGUAUUGAUAAUCUCUAAAAGUUGUUUACUAUUCUGCAUUUGAAUAUAUUUCUAAUUAAGAAAUAAGACCAUUUAUUUAUCUGGUAUUUGAUAUCAAACUUAUAGCAUUUAAAAUAUUUAACAUUUUAGAUUAUUGCUUAUAGCCCUAUAAUCUGCUGCCCUGUGGUUUGUUCCCUUUAGCAUAGUAAAAAUGAGUUUCCAAAAAAAGUCUAGAUCAUAUAAGAAAUACAUAGCAAAUGUUUUAUAUUGAGAGAAAAUGCAUUUUUCACAGUUUUGCCAAGAGUUUUUUUAAAUUUGGCAUUGAAAUGUACACAAAGAAGAAAAGCUUUAGUACAUUUUAUAUUAAUCAAAACAUUAAAUGCUGUUCCAAAUAGCUGUAGUGCAGUAAUAAUUGUAAUGUUUUGGAAAUAGGAAGCAGCAUAGCUUAUUUACUAUAUUAGUUGGUGGAAACUGAGCUACAUGUGUAUUUUAAAAAUAGCAGUUGAUUUUUCUUCCAUUGUAUGUGACACAUUGACGGGUUCUACUUUUUUUCAACUUCCUUUUGUUCUACUUAAGAACAAAUUCUCUAGGCAAGGAAGAAUAGAAAUUGUCACUUGGAUCUCAUGGACAUGGGUGUGGGGGAUGAAGAUGGGAGUUGGGAAUGAGGUGUUGAGACCAGCACUGGAGCAGCUACUUGGGUGUUGUUCAUGUCUCAUUAUUUUAUAUCAUGGCGAGUCUCACUCUCUCAUGUCAUCUUGGGCUGGUAUGGUGGAUUUUUGAACUGAAGCCUUAAAGGUGCCCCUUGGGUACCAGUAGACCCCUAUCAAGAUUAUGGCUUUCCUCAGAGAGGCAAGAGGAAUGCAGUUCACAUUAAGUGCCUACUACUGUGAGUCAUAUACUAAACUAGGAGCUUUCGUACGUUUGUAUCACUUAAACCUCACAGGAAACUCUCUAAAGUAUGGAAGGAAGGCACAGAGAGCUACUGUUAAAAUGUGGAGUGAUGACUGAAAGUCAUGUCUGCUUAAUUUCAGAGUUUGUGCUCUUGGGCUGGUUCUCAGAUGCAAGAAGUCCCACAAUCCAUCAACACUUCUAGGUUUGAAACAGCCCGAACACGUGAGAUAGUGACAGAAGAGUACGCAUCUUAGGUCCUAUGGUUUGUGGGGUACAUUAUCUUUUCUCAGCCUUCUUUCCUUCAGUUCAGAACAUUUGGAGGUUGAUUAUUCUAGAAAGGGAUUGCAACCUCUUCUGUCUUUGGCUAUUUUGUUAGGCCUGUGCUGUACUUGAAAAGACAGAGCAAUCUGGCAGGUGUUCUGCUUGGCGUCAAUAUAUGGAGCUUACAUCCUAUUGUUUUACCCCAGGCCCACUUUCCCCAUACCCCUGCAGACAGUGGAGUUUGUGAAGCAUUGUAUUCUCUUUUAGGCUGAUACGCAGGCAGAAAAAAUACCUGGGUCAUAGGAAUAUAUAUAAAUCUAGGGGAGUAAGGAAAUGGGGGAAUCUUCUUUUGGAGCUCUGAAAGUGUGUGUGUGUGUGUGUGUGUGUGUGUGUGUUUAAAUAGGGACGGUUAUGAAGGGAAAUUAAAUGUGAUUAAAAAUUAGUUAAAAAUUUUAGGCACUCUAUGGAUUAUAUAGGCGUUUGUAGAUUGACCCAGGAAUUAAUCAGCAUUUAUAGAUUUUAUUCUCUACAAAUAUGUGUUAAAAGUUCCGAAUAACCAACUUAUGGAUGGAUUUUGGAGAAAUAACCAGAGGAGCUGGCCAGCCUUUACUUUACCGUAAGGGUUGCUGAGAGUGUGCCCUGGGGGCUUCAGCUGCGGCUCUCCUCCCGAGAUGUGAUUUGGCUGCAUGAAUGGCAUGAACCUCUUAGGUAGAUUUGGUUUAUGAUCCCCACAACUUCAGUUAGAAUGUUACUUUCUCUCAAAUUGCCAUAGUAACAUGGUCACAUUUCACCUUAGAAGUGGUUGCUUCUUAUUGCAGGGUCUUUCUGAUGUGAUUUCUUAUAGCACCUCUCAAGAAAAUGAAGAAUAAACUUCAGGAUCCUUCAAACCAAAAAUGUGGUGGAAGAAAGAAAACCGUGUCUUUCAGCAGCAUGCCAUCGGAAAAGAAAAUUAGCAGUGCAAAUGACUGCAUCAGCUUCAUGCAAGCUGGCUGUGAGUUGAAGAAAGUCCGGCCAAAUUCUCGCAUUUACAACCGUUUUUUCACUCUGGACACAGACCUUCAAGCUCUUCGCUGGGAACCUUCAAAGAAAGACCUCGAGAAAGCCAAGCUUGAUAUUUCUGCCAUAAAAGAGAUCAGACUGGGGAAAAACACGGAAACAUUUAGAAACAAUGGCCUUGCUGACCAGAUCUGUGAGGACUGUGCCUUUUCCAUACUCCACGGGGAAAACUAUGAGUCUCUGGACCUAGUUGCCAAUUCAGCAGAUGUGGCAAACAUCUGGGUGUCUGGGUUACGGUACCUGGUUUCUCGAAGUAAGCAGCCUCUUGAUUUUAUGGAGGGCAACCAGAACACACCACGGUUCAUGUGGUUGAAAACAGUGUUUGAAGCAGCAGAUGUUGAUGGGAAUGGGAUUAUGUUGGAAGACACCUCUGUAGAGUUAAUAAAACAACUCAACCCUACUCUGAAGGAAGCCAAGAUCAGGUUAAAGUUUAAAGAAAUCCAGAAGAGCAAGGAAAAACUAACCACCCGCGUGACCGAAGAGGAAUUUUGUGAAGCUUUUUGUGAACUUUGCACCAGGCCAGAAGUGUAUUUCUUACUUGUACAGAUAUCUAAAAACAAAGAAUAUUUGGAUGCCAAUGAUCUCAUGCUCUUUUUAGAAGCUGAGCAAGGAGUCACCCAUAUCACCGAGGAUAUAUGCUUAGACAUCAUAAGGAGAUACGAACUUUCUGAAGAGGGACGUCAAAAAGGGUUUCUUGCAAUUGAUGGCUUUACCCAGUAUUUAUUGUCAUCAGAAUGUGACAUUUUUGAUCCUGAGCAAAAGAAGGUUGCCCAAGAUAUGACCCAGCCAUUAUCUCACUACUAUAUCAAUGCCUCUCAUAACACCUAUCUAAUAGAAGACCAGUUCAGGGGGCCAGCUGACAUCAAUGGGUACAUUAGAGCUUUGAAAAUGGGCUGUCGAAGCGUUGAACUCGAUGUAAGUGAUGGUUCAGAUAAUGAACCAAUCCUUUGUAAUCGAAAUAACAUGACAACCCAUGUUUCCUUUCGAAGUGUCAUAGAGGUAAUAAAUAAAUUUGCCUUUGUUGCUUCUGAAUACCCACUCAUUCUUUGCUUGGGAAAUCACUGCUCCUUGCCGCAGCAGAAGGUAAUGGCUCAACAGAUGAAAAAGGUCUUUGGCAAUAAACUCUAUACUGAAGCACCUUUGCCCUCAGAAUCCUACCUCCCAUCACCAGAAAAAUUAAAAAGAAUGAUCAUUGUGAAAGGAAAGAAGUUGCCUUCUGAUCCAGAUGUGUUAGAAGGAGAAGUAACAGAUGAAGAUGAAGAAGCUGAAAUGUCUCGAAGGAUGUCGGUAGAUUACAAUGGUGAGCAGAAGCAAAUCCGACUCUGUAGGGAGCUCUCUGAUUUGGUGUCUAUUUGUAAAUCUGUUCAAUACAGGGAUUUUGAACUAUCUAUGAAAAGCCAAAACUAUUGGGAAAUGUGUUCAUUUAGUGAAACAGAGGCCAGCCGCAUUGCAAAUGAGUACCCAGAGGAUUUUGUUAAUUAUAAUAAGAAGUUCUUAUCAAGAAUCUAUCCAAGUGCCAUGAGGAUCGAUUCCAGUAACUUGAAUCCACAGGACUUUUGGAAUUGUGGCUGUCAGAUUGUAGCAAUGAAUUUUCAGACUCCGGGUCCAAUGAUGGACCUUCACACGGGCUGGUUUCUUCAAAACGGGGGAUGUGGUUAUGUUCUAAGGCCGUCUAUAAUGCGAGAUGAAGUUUCUUACUUCAGCGCAAAUACAAAGGGCAUUCUACCUGGGGUGUCUCCUCUAGCUCUUCAUAUCAAGAUCAUCAGUGGUCAGAAUUUCCCAAAGCCCAAGGGAGCUUGUGCCAAAGGGGAUGUCAUAGAUCCCUAUGUUUGUAUAGAGAUACACGGAAUUCCAGCGGAUUGUUCGGAACAAAGAACUAAAACUGUACAGCAAAACAGUGAUAAUCCUAUUUUUGAUGAAACUUUUGAGUUCCAAGUAAACCUACCUGAGCUGGCCAUGAUCCGUUUUGUUGUUCUGGAUGAUGACUACAUUGGGGAUGAGUUUAUAGGGCAAUAUACGAUACCAUUUGAAUGUUUGCAGCCUGGAUAUCGGCAUGUUCCCCUGCGUUCUUUUGUGGGUGACAUCAUGGAGCACGUAACCCUUUUUGUCCACAUAGCAAUAACUAAUCGAAGUGGAGGAGGAAAGGCACAGAAGCGCAGUCUUUCAGUGAGAAUGGGGAAGAAAGUUCGGGAAUAUACCAUGCUCAGGAAUAUCGGUCUUAAAACCAUUGAUGACAUCUUUAAAAUAGCGGUUCAUCCAUUACGAGAAGCCAUAGAUAUGAGAGAAAAUAUGCAGAAUGCAAUCGUGUCUAUUAAGGAACUAUGUGGACUCCCUCCAAUUGCCAGUCUGAAGCAGUGCCUGUUAACUCUGUCAUCUCGGCUCAUCACCAGUGACAAUACUCCUUCAGUCUCACUUGUGAUGAAAGACAGCUUUCCUUACCUGGAGCCUCUGGGUGCAAUUCCAGAUGUGCAGAAAAAGAUGCUGACUGCUUAUGAUCUGAUGAUUCAAGAGAGCCGGUUUCUCAUAGAAAUGGCGGACACAGUCCAGGAAAAGAUUGUACAGUGUCAGAAAGCAGGGAUGGAGUUCCAUGAAGAACUUCAUAAUUUGGGGGCAAAAGAAGGCUUGAAGGGAAGAAAACUCAACAAAGCAACUGAGAGCUUUGCUUGGAACAUUACAGUAUUGAAGGGCCAAGGAGAUCUGUUGAAGAAUGCCAAGAAUGAAGCUAUAGAAAACAUGAAGCAGAUCCAGCUGGCAUGCCUGUCCUGUGGACUGAGUAAAGCCCCCAGCAGCAGUGCUGAGGCCAAGAGCAAGCGCAGCCUGGAAGCCAUAGAGGAGAAGGAAAGUAGUGAGGAGAAUGGGAAGCUGUGACUCUGGGCAUUAUCGACACGUUCACCCAUCUUAUCAAGGACUCUGGUUUCUCAUUCUUGUUUUCUUUCUUUAAAUGUUUUAUAAGUUCACAAAAUGGUGCCCUAUAUGGGGUAUUGGACAUAGAUAUUUUCACAAUGUCAGUAUUUCAGUGUAGUUAAUUUAUCUAAAUUAAAGCCUUUAGUAUCAGUGUUUUAAAUUCUGAGACAUGUGUCAACACCCCUGUGUGGAUGCCUGUGGAAGAGUGUGUGUGUGUGUGUGUGUGUGUGUGUGUGGCAGAGAGAGAGAAAGAGAGAGAGAGAGAGAAAUUCUGUUAAAAUCUAUUCUGUGUUGCAUUAUUCAUUUAGUGAGUUAUUCCUUGAUCAUUUUGGGACAAUUGUUUUAAUCUGAAAUUCUAAAGAGCACUUACUGUAACCUGUUGCUGUGUUUAAUUUGACUUCUCUGCCUUUGACAUUUAAUUUAGUGAUCUUAGCAUAGCUUAUUAUUGAAGGAAGCCAAAUUUAUCAAAGCAUAGAUGUUUUGGUAGAUUAAAUAUAGAUUAGAAAAAUUCCUAAGAAUCAGAGUAGAAAUAAAAGUGAAUGAAAGAUUAAACAGAUGAUGAGAAUUUCUAAAAAGAUUAGCAAGGUCAUUUCUUCAGUCAGAAAACUUUAAAAAAUAUUUAUUAAAUAAAAUCAAUUUUUAGGAAGUUUUCUGUAGUCAUUUACUAAACAUAUGAUUUCACUAGAAAAGCUGAUCAUAAGUGAAUUUAUACCUACCUGUGUGGUACUCUGAAACACACUGAAAGCUCUGUUGCAAUUAGGAUUUUGAUGUGACAAUAAUAUUGUUGUAUAAUUUCGAGAUUUGUAGGAAGGUCUCAUUCUUCCAAGCUGAGAGUCUAGCACUCAUUUUCUAUAACAGAUAUGGCAGCUUAGAGGUGUUGGCUUUGUUUGGAUGUAAUUUAGGGUACUAAAUUUAAAUUUAAAGAUAUUGUUCAAACAAUAUCAUAUCAUCACAUUGAGCUGAUAUAAAUUCUGUGGGUCCGAUAAUAUCUUUGUGAUAAUUUAAGAGCUAACCAGUUACCACACAUCUAUGAUAUAACCCUAACACACACAGAAAAGCAUACAUGCAAAAAGAAAUGACUAAUUAGGGUACAUUUAUAAUUGCAUCUAGGUAAUUUUUACCCUAAUGUCUUCAUAAAGUACUUGAGUGUAAUGUUUGUUACCUCCAACAGAACUAAAUGUUCUAUGGUUAUGAAAGAAUAUAUUUAUUUAAAGCAUUGCUUUUAUUUUGAAAAGCUUCUUAAUUAAUUUGAUUAACAAAUAUGCUAAUUUGGGGAAACCUAGAGAAGAUAAUUGUUGAAAUUUUGCAAAUAUAAACAUCUCCUAUAGCUUCUGUGUUAUUUCUGACUUCUUAACACUAUUAUGUUUAUGUUGCACAUUACUGAAAGAGUAAAGAUAUGAAAAAAACACUUAUUGUUUUCUUUUAUUGUGAAUUGAAAAAGCAAAGCUAAUGAAAAUGGGUUACUACAUCAAAAAUAUCUUAAAGAGUUUGCUAUUUCCAUGGACCAGAUAUGAUGAAAUUAUUCCCUGGGUUUAAAACUGGGCACUCGAGGAGGAGGUACCUGAAGUCAUUUGAAGGCAAGUUUCCAAUGAUGCUACAAUGGCCUGAAAAAAUUUCUUUACCCUCUGUUAUAUUUAACUUGCUGGUAGGAGGAAUAGUGGAAUGCAGGUGUUAAGCCCUUUGUGGUGAAAAAGAGGUUCUAUAGACAGAAACAAAACCCACCUUACAUCAGCUGAUUGGUUGAUUUUACUAGUGUACCUCUUCAUCUACUUGAAUUCUAUUUGGUAAAUCCAUGUCUUUACUGGAUAUACAGUUAGGUGGGAAGAGGAGAUAAAGGAUGACAAACUCUCAAACAAUAUUUAUACAUUUAUUUACUCCAGGGUCAAAUCCAAUCCUUGGAAGUAGCUUCUCUAGUUUAUUUUAUUUGUCCCAGAGCUCUACUCACACUUAGGACCCACCCAAAAAUUCUCAAAAACGUAAUAUGGAUUCUGCCUCAUCUGAUGCUAUUUCUGGCAGUGGGUUGUCAGCCAUACUCUGCUUCAUUCCACUGGGUGUCCUUGCUAGAUGGGGAGUGAGAUGUGGAGCAGGGAGGAGCUUUGGAUUCUGGGAGUGGAGGUGGCAAGGGAAAAGUCUCCUAGUCUCCUGUGAUGUUCCUGCCUCCAGAUAGAAUAGCAAAAACAAACAAUUUUUUUUUGUGUAUUAUGCCUCCAUGACAUUGUUACAUUCUAUGAGGAGCAUCUGUCUCCUUUCUAGACUUGAACUGUGGUAGAAAAAGCCCCCUUCUCUCUUCUAUCUACUUAGAUUUGGUGAUGCUAGGAAUGUAGUGUUUUAGAUAUUAAUUCUAUUUUUAUUUAUUCAUUUUUACAUCACCAAUAGGAUCUGAGGUGGAGAUGGCGGGUAUUAUCACUGGCAUUUUACAGGUGAGAAAGCCCAAAGCCACUGAGGUAAUUAAUGGAAUAAUUGAUUUUGAACUUGGGUCUGUCUGAUUUCAUGUGCAAGAUUAUAUACUUAGUGAUUUUGAUUUUAAGUUUAUUCUUAACAUUUUAAACCAGACUAUUAACUCUUACCUUUAUAACCACAGAUACAAAGAACUGUAUCAUUUAUUUUCUGAAUAUAAAAUAUUAAUGGUCAAUAUAAAAAUACAAAAAUAGAGAACUAUAUACAACAGAAAAGCAAAAUUACCCACUAAUAACAUUUUGAUUUAUAUCCCUUUAGACACUGUUUAGAGUUUAUACAUAUAUGUAAAUAUGCUUGUAUUUUAACAAAAUUGAGAUAUUAUAUAAACUGUUUGUAGCAGGGUGUUUAAAAUUUUAACAAUAUGUUAUGGAUAUCUUUCUGUGUCAAUAAAUGUGUAUUUACAUUAGA